GAAGGGGUGGCGCUGCGAUCCCGCAGGGCAGCGACGCGACUCUGGUGCGGGCCGUCUUCUUCCCCCCGAGCUGGGCGUGCGCGGCCGCAAUGAACUGGGAGCUGCUGCUGUGGCUGCUGGUGCUGUGCGCGCUGCUCCUGCUCUUGGUGCAGCUGCUGCGCUUCCUGAGGGCUGACGGCGACCUGACGCUACUAUGGGCCGAGUGGCAGGGACGACGCCCAGAAUGGGAGCUGACUGAUAUGGUGGUGUGGGUGACUGGAGCCUCGAGUGGAAUUGGUGAGGAGCUGGCUUACCAGUUGUCUAAACUAGGAGUUUCUCUUGUGCUGUCAGCCAGAAGAGUGCAUGAGCUGGAAAGGGUGAAAAGAAGAUGCCUAGAGAAUGGCAAUUUAAAAGAAAAAGAUAUACUUGUUUUGCCCCUUGACCUGACCGACACUGGUUCCCAUGAAGCGGCUACCAAAGCUGUUCUCCAGGAGUUUGGUAGAGUAAGUAAUCGACAUUCUGGUCAACAAUGGUGGAAUGUCCCAGCGUUCUCUGUGCAUGGAUACCAGCUUGGAUGUCUACAGAAAGCUAAUAGAGCUUAACUACUUAGGGACGGUGUCCUUGACAAAAUGUGUUCUGCCUCACAUGAUCGAGAGGAAGCAAGGAAAGAUUGUUACUGUGAAUAGCAUCCUGGGUAUCAUAUCUGUACCUCUUUCCAUUGGAUACUGUGCUAGCAAGCAUGCUCUCCGGGGUUUUUUUAAUGGCCUUCGAACAGAACUUGCCACAUACCCAGGUAUAAUAGUUUCUAACAUUUGCCCAGGACCUGUGCAAUCAAAUAUUGUGGAGAAUUCCCUAGCUGGAGAAGUCACAAAGACUAUAGGCAAUAAUGGAGACCAGUCCCACAAGAUGACAACCAGUCGUUGUGUGCGGCUGAUGUUAAUCAGCAUGGCCAAUGAUUUGAAAGAAGUUUGGAUCUCAGAACAACCUUUCUUGUUAGUAACAUAUUUGUGGCAAUACAUGCCAACCUGGGCCUGGUGGAUAACCAACAAGAUGGGGAAGAAAAGGAUUGAGAACUUUAAGAGUGGUGUGGAUGCAGACUCUUCUUAUUUUAAAAUCUUUAAGACAAAACAUGACUGAAAAGAGCACCUGUACUUUUCAAGCCACUGGAGGGAGAAAUGGAAAACAUGAAAACAGCAAUCUUCUUAUGCUUCUGAAUAAUCAAAGACUAAUUUGUGAUUUUACUUUUUAAUAGAUAUGACUUUGCUUCCAACAUGGAAUGAAAUAAAAAAUAAAUAAUAAAAGAUUGCCAUGAAUCUUGCAAAAAAGGUAUUAACUCAUACUAUAUUCUUGGAUAAAAUAACCUUUUAAAAUACUUUAGCACAUAUGCUUAAAAUCUAAGUUAACAGAUUUGUCUUAGUCCAUUUGUGCUGCUAUAACAAAAUACCACAGAUUUGGUAAUUUAUAAACAACAGAAAUCUGUUUUUCCUGGCUCUUGAGGCUGGGAAUUCCAAGACCAAUGCACCAGCAGAAUUAGUGUCUGGUGAAGGCUGAUCUCUGCUUCCAAGAUGGCACCUCAUUGCUGCAUCCUCCACAGUGGAGGAAUGUAUGUCCUCACAUGGUGGAAGGGACAGAAGGGAAAGAGGAGCAAAAUGCUUUCAAAAGAGCAUUUAAUCUCAUUCAUUACUCAGUCACCUCUUAAAGGCCACAUCCUUUAAUACUGUUGCUUUGGGGAUUAAGUUUCGACAUGAAUUUUGGAGGGGACAAAAACAUCCAAACCAUAGCAACAUAAAUGUAUAGAAUAUUUCACACAAAGCAGAGUGCUGGGUAAUGACCAGAUAUAAAGAAGUAUUUGAAAUGACCUUACCUCCAAGAUGCUUAUACUCUUAGAAAAGUUGACAGGUACAGAUGGCUGUAAUUUGAAGCAGCAGGUAGGAUUCAUUGCACCUAUUAUUCAUUAAACACCUGUUGUAUGUCUUCUACUGUA